GCGGCCCUGGCCAGAAGCGGAGGAGGUGGCACCCGGGACCGAGCUGGGGUCUUGGAGGAAGAGAGGAUGGCGUCGUCGAGCCCUGACUCCCCAUGUUCCUGCGACUGCUUUGUCUCCGUGCCCCCGGCCUCAGCCAUCCCGGCUGUGAUCUUUGCCAAGAACUCGGACCGACCCCGGGACGAGGUGCAGGAGGUGGUGUUUGUCCCCGCAGGCACUCACACUCCUGGGAGCCGGCUCCAGUGCACCUACAUUGAAGUGGAACAGGUGUCGAAGACGCACGCUGUGAUUCUGAGCCGUCCUUCUUGGCUAUGGGGGGCUGAGAUGGGCGCCAACGAGCAUGGUGUCUGCAUUGGCAACGAGGCUGUGUGGACGAAGGAGCCAGUUGGGGAGGGGGAAGCCCUGCUGGGCAUGGACCUACUCAGGCUGGCUUUGGAACGGAGCAGCUCUGCCCAGGAGGCCUUGCAUGUGAUCACAGGGUUACUGGAGCACUAUGGGCAGGGGGGCAACUGCCUGGAGGAUGCUGCGCCAUUCUCCUACCAUAGCACCUUCCUGCUGGCUGACCGCACUGAGGCGUGGGUGCUGGAGACAGCUGGGAGGCUCUGGGCUGCACAGAGGAUCCAGGAGGGGGCCCGCAACAUCUCCAACCAGCUGAGCAUUGGCACGGACAUCUCGGCCCAACACCCGGAGCUGCGGACUCAUGCCCAGGCCAAGGGCUGGUGGGAUGGGCAGGGUGCCUUUGACUUUGCUCAGAUCUUCUCCCUGACCCAGCAGCCUGUGCGCAUGGAGGCUGCCAAGGCCCGCUUCCAGGCAGGGCGGGAGCUGCUGCGGCAACGGCAAGGGGGCAUCACGGCAGAGGUGAUGAUGGGCAUCCUCAGAGACAAGGAGAGUGGUAUCUGUAUGGACUCGGGAGGCUUUCGCACCACGGCCAGCAUGGUGUCUGUCCUGCCCCAGGAUCCCACGCAGCCCUGCGUGCACUUUCUUACCGCCACGCCAGACCCAUCCAGGUCUGUGUUCAAACCUUUCAUCUUCGGGAUGGGGGUGGCCCAGGCCCCCCAGGUGCUGUCCCCCACUUUUGGAGCACAAGACCCUGUUCGGACCCUGCCCCGAUUCCAGACUCAGGUAGAUCGUCGGCAUACCCUCUACCGUGGACACCAGGCAGCCCUGGGGCUGAUGGAGAGAGAUCAGGUAUCCCCCAGGGAGUAGGGGCUACCUUGAGGGGAUGAUAGACCUCCCCCACUCCCAGUGGGACUCUGGAAAUAUGAAGGAACUAGGGAGUGGAAGAGAUUUCAGAGCUGGGGAGAGGAGUUCCUCCCUUCAAAGCCAGCAACUGCCUUUGGGGAAUGUCGGGGGGUAUCUCCUUUCUCCUGCUUGUGUGAGGUGGUACACAGUCCCCCCUUCACCUGGCGGGAAGCCUGUCCCGGACAGACUCAUCUCAGCUUUCCCUUGGGGCAGGAUCGGGGGCAGCAGCUCCAGCAGAAACAGCAGGAUCUGGAGCAGGAAGGCCUCGAGGCCACACAGGGGCUGCUGGCCGGCGAGUGGGCCCCACCCCUCUGGGAGCUGGGCAGCCUCUUCCAGGCCUUCGUGAAGAGGGAGAGCCAGGCUUAUGCGUAAGCUUCAUAGCUUCUGCUGGCCUGGGGUGGACCCAGGACCCCUGGGGCCUGGGUGCCCUGAGUGGUGGUAAAGUGGAGCAAUCCCUUCACGCUCCUUGGCCAUGUUCUGAGCGGCCAGCUUGGCCUUUGCCUUAAUAAAUGUGCUUUAUUUUC